CUCCCAAAGUGCUGAGCCACCGCGCCCAGCCACAUUUCUCUUUCUUAAAUUACAAAAAAUAUGAGGAGGCAGAUCGCUUUGAUCACUCCCCUCCUCCUCCCAUCAACCCUCUAAAUAUACACACAUGUGUAUACACACGCCAUCUCUUACACACAUAUACACUCACAGAUGGACCCUUGGUAGCAAAUCUCUAGAUUAAGUAGCUAUUAAGAGCAUAAGCUUUGGAGUUAGACCAGGUGAGAAUUCUGCCUCCAUCACUAGCUGGCUACAGGCAAGUCUUUAUUCCUCUGAGCCUCAGUUUCCUCCUCUGUAAAAUGGGAUUCUAACGUGAACCUCACAUGAUUCCUGUGAGGAUUGAGAAAACAUGAAAAGCACCAGGCAGGGGCACAUAAGGUCCUGCCUGGGGCUUCUCCCUGCCUGCCCUGGCCCACAGCACUUCACCACUGCUCUUCAAUAGAGCCUUCCCAACCUCUGGCUUACCCCCACAUGGUUUCUUUCUUGCCCCUAGAGUGUGGGCAUUCUGUCUUGGGCUUUUCUCUCUCUUCCCCAUCCACCCUCCUCAAUGUCUGACGUAGAGCUGAACACCCAAGAGGAGUUUGCAACCAUUGUUUAAUUUAGUCGAAUAACUGGAUUCUGUCUUUAAAAUCCCUAUUUUUUAAAAUAAAAUAAAUCCCUUUUUAAAAUAAAAUCCCUAUUUAUUGUCUAAGAUUAAAAAAAAAUCCCUGUCCCAAGCCAACUCAGUUAUGUUAUUUUCUUCCCCUUUUCCCAAAACACUGGUGCUUUAACACAAACACAUGCAGUCACAUACACACCAGGGCAGGCCCUGAGUAAUGACAGGAACCACACCCGCAAUGGUGUCUGUGCACCGGGCACUGAGCUCAGGAUCUUACCUGCCUUUGCGCAUUUAAUUUUUAUUCAGACCUCACAGACACACCGCCAGGUAUUGUGAUUCCCCCUUGCACCCCGGGCAUAACAGACUCAGGGAGGGGAAGGGACUUGCCCAGGUAGGCCCAGUGCACACGGGGCUGUCCAUACUUCACCAGCCAGCUGAGGCGGCUGGGGAGGGAGGUGGCCAGCCUCACAAACAAAGGUGUGGGCAUUCCAAUCCAUCACUGCGCCCAGCGGGGUGGGGACCUGGCGGGAAGGCCCAAGAGAGUGUCAUAGGUCAGCAAGCCCAGGAUCCCUGGUAUGCACGCAUGCGUGUCCACACGUGCGCACGCGCACAGACACACACACGCGCACACACACACGACUCCACAAUUCUGAGUGGUUUGAUUUGGUUCAGCUCCAUGAGGAGGUAGAUGAAGCUGGAUGAUAUCCCAGGCACUGUGCACACAAGUGCUUUUCAUCGAUUAUCUCAUUUGAUCAUCACAGAAAUGCUGGCAAAUCCAUUAACCCCAUUCUAUAGACAGCAAACUAAGGCACAGAGAGGCGUUGUGUCUUGCCCAAGGGCACGUGUGGCUGACAGGAACUGAACUCAGGUCUAUGGGACAUCAAAGCCCAGGAGGAGAGACAGCUUUCCUAAGGGUCUGGCUCCAGCCUUAUGUGGUCUUGGGGUGCUCACCUUUGCAUAUCAGUGCCCUCUAAGUUUGCUACUGGCUUCUCUCCCCACUUAGCUGGGAAGUUUGAGAGCUGGGUACCCUCCUCCUCAUAGAUACAGAAGCCCAGAGAGAAAGCUGAUUUUAGCAUCAUCCAGCCCAACCACCUCUUUUACAGGAGAAAAGAUGAUGUAUGUGAGAGUGCAGCACAGCACAGACCCACGGGAGGAGCUGAGAAAAUUCAGGCAUCACUGUUGUUACUGCAGAGGAUCCCGAUGGAGGAGAAAAGGGGCUGGUAUUUCACCAUGGCAACACUCUACAUCAGGCUAGAUGGCAUCUUCCUGGAGCUGGGCAGUGAGGAGCAGAAGAGACUGCCUGCCUUCAACCGCACGCUGGCCCUACUCCGGCAAGUGCUGAAGUCCGAGGACCCCCGCCACCGAGCCCUGGCCUGGUGCUACCUCGGGAUGCUGCUGGAGCGGAAGGACACCUUCUCCACCACCCCCAUGGGCGUCCAUGACUGCGGGUACUCAGGGACCGACCCUCUAGACUGCUUCGGCAAGGCCAUUGAGAUUGCCAAGAACCAACCUCCCAUCCUGAAUCGCCUGGCAAAAAUCUUCUACUUCCUGGGAAAGCAGGAUAUGGCCAUUGGAACCUGCAACAUGGCCCUGGAUGUCCUACGAGAUCCAGAACUCAACUGGCAGGCGUACUGCACAAGGGCCAAGAUCCACAUCAGAGCCUACCUGCAUGACCUCAAGCGGGCCAAGAUGGGUCUCGGGGGCAUGCCUGACAGGAACCACCUGGCCUGUGCCAAGGCUGACCUUGAGGAAGUGGUCAGGGUGUGCCCAGGCUUCAAGGCGUACCUGGACAUCGGCCAGGUCUACUACUAUAUGGGCGUGGACGCGGUGCAGGAGCUGCUGGCGGUGGACGAGGCGGCGCUGAACCAGGCGCUGGUGUUCCUGGCCAAGGCGGGCGAGUCGGAGCUGGGUGCCACGCUGCCCGAGCUGCAGCUGCUGCGCGGCAAGUGCCUGCGCAUCAAGGGCGAGGACGCCAACGCGGCCGCCUGCUUCAAGCGCGCAGUGGAGCUGGACGACGCGGGCUCCAGCCACACCGACGGCUUCGGCUGCCUGCUCGAGGCGCUGCUGGCGCAGUGGAGCCAGGCACAGCUGAGCGACGGGGAGCUGGGCCGCGAGGUGGACGCCUGGCUGCGCCGCGCCCAGGACAAGUACCCCGCGGCGCGCCUGCGCCAGGAGCUGCAGCGCGUGUGGCGCGGGCACACGGACGAGGUGUUGGGGCUGGCCCGGGCCCUGGUGGCCCAGGGACGGCCGGCGCUGGUGCGGCUGCUCUUCGAGACCAUGGAGCGCGAGGGCGAGGGCGCCAGCGCGCCGCGGGACCGCCGGGCUGUCUCAUUCUAGGGCUCAGGUGCCCAGGCCGGAGGCUCCCUGGGACCCCGCCCAGGCCCCGCCCAGCUGAUGGGACCAGGUCCGGAUGGACUCCCUGCCUUAGGCUGACCUGGGAGCGGAGCCAGUUCGAUUCUUGGUCGGGAAUUGUGAAUGGGGAUGUUGCGACACCCGCGCGGUUUGAAACGCCCACCCAGACUGGAAGGCCUGAUUCCCGAGAGCAGAAGAGGCUGGGAGCAGAGGUGAGAAAACACUGGGAAGCUGCCAAUUAAGGGACAGAAUUUUCUAGACAUACAGGUAAAAUAAGAUGGUUGUGAGGCUUCUGAGAGAAACAGAAGACAGCUACCUCAGUGUGGCAGUUUUCUAGUCCGGGCGCUCAAUCCCUCAGGCCUGAGUGCCUGUCUUUGGACUCCGGUAGGCCACACUCUAUCCUUAUGAGAAAGCCCCGUUUACUUUAGUUGACUGGAGUGUGGUCUCAGCUCCUGCAGCCAGAAAAGCCCUGACUAAAGCAGAGGGCAGGGUGGCACGGCGAGUGAGUUACGGGACAGGGCCCUAGCCUAAGCCUCGUGCUCAGGGCUCAUUCCUGCCUCUCUGCUACUUUUCUAGUAGGCCUCCUUCUUGGUCCGCUUGGCCCAAAAGGCCUCCCAAAUGCUCUGAAAUAGAGCUCAUCAAUAGAACCUUCACUUGAUUUCCCUCUUCUUGGGGGAAACUAAGGGCGCCACCCAUUAGGAGGUGCCACCUGCCCCCCCCCUUUUUUUUUUUUUUUUUUGAGAGGGAGUUUCGCUCUUGUUGCCCAUGCUGGAGUGCAAUGGCACGAUCUUGGCCCACUGCAACCUCCAUCUCCUGGGUUCAAGCGAUCUUCCCGCCUCAGCCUUCCAAGUAGCUGGGAUUACAGACGUGUGCCAUCAGGCCUGGCUAAUUUUGUAUUUUUAGUAGAGACAGGGUUUCGCCAUGUUGGUCAGGAUGGUCUCGAACUCCUGACCUCAACUGAUCCACCCGCCUCAGCCUCCCAAAGUGCUAGGAUUACAGGUGUGAGCCACUGCACCCGGCCCUGCCCCCAGUCUUGACCAUUCUACUAAUUUUAAAGAACAUCUUGGAAUUUUACACUCUUGGAAUCAUAGUCGUAGAAUCCUUUUUUUGAGACAGAGUCUCACUCUGUCGCCCAGGCUGGAGUGCAGUGGCCAGAUCUCAGCUCACUGAAACCUCAGCCUCCCAAGUUCAAGUGAUUCUCGUACCUCAGCCUCCUGAGUAGCUGGAAUUCCAGGCUGUACUCACUGCUUUGCUCAUAUCCUCGCUCAUUACCAGGGACAGGCCAGCACCCCUGCAUUGCAUCUCACAUAUCCACUGAUGGAUGGAGAACAGACUGAAAUUCAGUGCCUUAGAGACCACACACUCCAACCCCCUCAUUGUGCAGAUGGGAAAACUGAGAGCCAUAGAAGGGAAGUGGCUUGCCCAAAGCCACACUUACUGUUUUCCCCACACUGUACCACAAACUUUCACCAUUCUUCAGGUUUGGAAAAAUACUAAUAAACUGAUCAACACUAAA